ACUCGGGGGGCGGAACAUCCUGGAGGCUGGGGGUGGGGACAGGGACCAGGAAGUUGGGCCCGGGCCGCCGGGGCUGGGAAUUCGGAGACUAUAGCGUCCCCGCCCCGGGUUGGGAAGUGGGAAGUGGCACAGGAGCUAGGAUCCAGAAGCCCAGAGGCUCAGCGGUGCUUCUGGAGUUCCAGUGAUCCCGGAGUCUGAACCGGCAGUGAGAGUGGGGAAAGAGGGCUAGGCUAACAGUGCUGGCAUGGCAGGCGGGCCUGGUACUGGCCUUGUUGCCCUGGCUUGGCCACUGGUCUGCUGGCUGUCUCUGUGCCUGUGGACCCUGAGUGAGCCUUAACCUACUAUCUGGGCACUGUGGUUGCCAGGAUGCCGUGCGCAUGCUCAAUACCCUGCAGACCAAUGCCGGCUACCUGGAGCAGGUGAAGCGCCAGCGGGGUGACCCUCAGACACAGUUGGAAGCCAUGGAACUGUACCUGGCACGGAGUGGGCUGCAGGUGGAGGACUUGGACCGGCUGAACAUCAUCCACGUCACUGGGACGAAGGGGAAGGGCUCCACCUGUGCCUUCACGGAAUGUAUCCUCCGAAGCUAUGGCCUGAAGACGGGAUUCUUUAGCUCUCCCCACCUGGUGCAGGUUCGGGAGCGGAUCCGCAUCAAUGGGCAGCCCAUCAGUCCUGAGCUCUUCACCAAGUACUUCUGGCGCCUCUACCACCGGCUGGAGGAGACCAAGGAUGGCAGCUGUGUCUCCAUGCCCCCCUACUUCCGCUUCCUGACACUCAUGGCCUUCCACGUCUUCCUCCAAGAGAAGGUGGACCUGGCAGUGGUGGAGGUGGGCAUUGGCGGGGCUUAUGACUGCACCAACAUCAUCAGGAAGCCUGUGGUGUGCGGAGUCUCCUCUCUUGGCAUCGACCACACCAGCCUCCUGGGGGAUACGGUGGAGAAGAUCGCAUGGCAGAAAGGGGGCAUCUUUAAGCAAGGUGUCCCUGCCUUCACUGUGCUCCAACCUGAAGGUCCCCUGGCAGUGCUGAGGGACCGAGCCCAGCAGAUCUCAUGUCCUCUAUACCUGUGUCCGAUGCUGGAGGCCCUCGAGGAAGGGGGGCCGCCGCUGACCCUGGGCCUGGAGGGGGAGCACCAGCGGUCCAACGCCGCCUUGGCCUUGCAGCUGGCCCACUGCUGGCUGCAGCGGCAGGACCGCCAUGGUGCUGGGGAGCCAAAGGCAUCCAGGCCAGGGCUCCUGUGGCAGCUGCCCCUGGCACCUGUGUUCCAGCCCACAUCCCACAUGCGGCUCGGGCUUCGGAACACGGAGUGGCCGGGCCGGACGCAGGUGCUGCGGCGCGGGCCCCUCACCUGGUACCUGGACGGUGCGCACACCGCCAGCAGCGCGCAGGCCUGCGUGCGCUGGUUCCGCCAGGCGCUGCAGGGCCGCGAGAGGCCGAGCGGUGGCCCCGAGGUUCGAGUCUUGCUCUUCAAUGCUACCGGGGACCGGGACCCGGCGGCCCUGCUGAAGCUGCUGCAGCCCUGCCAGUUUGACUAUGCCGUCUUCUGCCCUAACCUGACAGAGGUGUCAUCCACAGGCAACGCAGACCAACAGAACUUCACAGUGACACUGGACCAGGUCCUGCUCCGCUGCCUGGAACACCAGCAGCACUGGAACCACCUGGACGAAGAGCAGGCCAGCCCGGACCUCUGGAGUGCCCCCAGCCCAGAGCCCGGUGGGUCCGCAUCCCUGCUUCUGGCGCCCCACCCACCCCACACCUGCAGUGCCAGCUCCCUCGUCUUCAGCUGCAUUUCACAUGCCUUGCAAUGGAUCAGCCAAGGCCGAGACCCCAUCUUCCAGCCACCUAGUCCCCCAAAGGGCCUCCUCACCCACCCUGUGGCUCACAGUGGGGCCAGCAUACUCCGUGAGGCUGCUGCCAUCCAUGUGCUAGUCACUGGCAGCCUGCACCUGGUGGGUGGUGUCCUGAAGCUGCUGGAGCCCGCACUGUCCCAGUAGCCAAGGCCCGGGGUUGGAGGUGGGAGCUUCCCACACCUGCCUGCGUUCUCCCCAUGAACUUACAUACUAGGUGCCUUUUGUUUUUGGCUUUCCUGGUUCUGUCUAGACUGGCCUAGGGGCCAGGGCUUUGGGAUGGGAGGCCGGGAGAGGAUGUCUUUUUUAAGGCUCUGUGCCUUGGUCUCUCCUUCCUCUUGGCUGAGAUAGCAGAGGGGCUCCCCGGGUCUCUCACUGUUGCAGUGGCCUGGCCGUUCAGCCUGUCUCCCCCAACACCCCGCCUGCCUCCUGGCUCAGGCCCAGCUUAUUGUGUGCGCUGCCUGGCCAGGCCCUGGGUCUUGCCAUGUGCUGGGUGGUAGAUUUCCUCCUCCCAGUGCCUUCUGGGAAGGGAGAGGGCCUCUGCCUGGGACACUGCGGGACAGAGGGUGGCUGGAGUGAAUUAAAGCCUUUGUUUUUUAAAGAAAUGGCAAAGCCUUCGACUGA